AGAUUUUUCAGUACCACUGGUUUUGAGCAGUCUGAUGAGGAUGUGCUUUGGUGUAUUGAGGUGUCUGAUGAGGGUGUGCUUUGGUGUAUUGAGGAGUCUGAUGAGAAUGUGCUUUGGUGUAUUGAGGUGUCUGAUGAGGAUGUGCUUUGGUGUAUUGAGUCUGAUGAGGAUGUGCUUUGGUGUAUUGAGUCUGAUGAGGAUGUGCUUUGGUGUAUUGAGGUGUCUGAUGAGAAUGUGCUUUGGUGUAUUGAGUCUGAUGAGGAUGUGCUUUGGUGUAUUGAGGUGACUGAUGAGAAUGUGCUUUGGUGUAUUGAGGUGUCUGAUGAGGGUGUGCUUUGGUGUAUUGAGGUGUCUGAUGAGGAUGUGCUUUGGUGUAUUGAGGAGUCUGAUGAGGAUGUGCUUUGGUGUAUUGAGUCCGAUGAGGAUGUGCUUUGGUGUAUUGAGGUGUCUGAUGAGAAUGUGCUUUGGUGUAUUGAGUCUGAUGAGAAUGUGCUUUGGUGUAUUGAGUCUGAUGAGGAUGUGCUUUGGUGUAUUGAGGUGUCUGAUGAGAAUGUGCUUUGGUGUAUUGAGUCUGAUGAGGAUGUGCUUUGGUGUAUUGAGGAGUCUGAUGAGGAUGUGCUUUGGUGUAUUGAGUCUGAUGAGGAUGUGCUUUGGUGUAUUGAGGUGUCUGAUGAGAAUGUGCUUUGGUGUAUUGAGUCUGAUGAGAAUGUGCUUUGGUGUAUUGAGUCUGAUGAGGAUGUGCUUUGGUGUAUUGAGGUGUCUGAUGAGAAUGUGCUUUGGUGUAUUGAGGAGUCUGAUGAGGAUGUGCUUUGGUGUAUUGAUGAGGAUGUGCUUUGGUGUAUUGAGGUGUCUGAUGAGGAUGUGCUUUGGUGUAUUGAGUCUGAUGAGAAUGUGCUUUGGUGUAUUGAGUCUGAUGAGAAUGUGCUUUGGUGUAUUGAGUCUGAUGAGGAUGUGCUUUGGUGUAUUGAGGAGUCUGAUGAGGAUGUGCUUUGGUGUAUUGAGUCUGAUGAGGAUGUGCUUUGGUGUAUUGAGGUGUCUGAUGAGGAUGUGCUUUGGUGUAUUGAGUCUGAUGAGGAUGUGCUUUGGUGUAUUGAGUCUGAAGAGGAUGUGCUGUGGUGUAUUGAGGUGUCUGAUGAGGAUGUACUUUGGUGUAUUGAGGUGUCUGAUGAGGAUGUGCUUUGGUGUAUUGAGGAGUCUGAUGAGGAUGUGCUUUGGUGUAUUGAGUCUGAUGAGGAUGUGCUUUGGUGUAUUGAGGUGUCUGAUGAGAAUGUGCUUUGGUGUAUUGAGGAGUCUGAUGAGGAUGUGCUUUGGUGUAUUGAGGAGUCUGAUGAGGAUGUGCUUUGGUGUAUUGAGGAGUCUGAUGAGGAUGUGCUUUGGUGUAUUGAGUCUGAUGAGGAUGUGCUUUGGUGUAUUGAGGAGUCUGAUGAGGAUGUGCUUUGGUGUAUUGAGUCUGAUGAGGAUGUGCUUUGGUGUAUUGAGGUGUCUGAUGAGAAUGUGCUUUGGUGUAUUGAGGUGUCUGAUGAGGGUGUGCUUUGGUGUAUUGAGUCUGAUGAGGAUGUGCUGUGGUGUAUUGAGGUGUCUGAUGAGGAUGUGCUUUGGUGUACUGAGGUGUCUGAUGAGGAUGUACUUUGGUGUAUUGAGGUGUCUGAUGAGGAUGUGCUUUGGUGUAUUGAGGAGUCUGAUGAGGAUGUGCUUUGGUGUAUUGAGGAGUCUGAUGAGGAUGUGCUUUGGUGUAUUGAGUCUGAUGAGGAUGUGCUUUGGUGUAUUGAGUCUGAUGAGGAUGUGCUUUGGUGUAUUGACGAGGAUGUGCUUUGGUGUAUUGAGGUGUCUGAUGAGGAUGUGCUUUGGUGUACACGUACAGUAUGUAGCCUUUGAGAUUGGCUUCUUUCAUAUUCACUGAAGGCUUCGCCAUGUCUUUUCGUGGCUUGAUGGCUCAUUUCUUUUUCGCGCUGGAUGAUACUCCAUCCUGGGCGUGUGCUGCAGCUUGUUUAUCUACGUACCUAUUGAAGGACAUCUUAGCUUCCAAGCUUCGGCAGUUACGCGUAAAGACAUCUUAGCAGCUUCCAAGCUUUGGCAGUUACACAUAAAGACAUCUUAGCAGCUUCCAAGCUUCAGCAGUUACUCAUAAAGCUGCUGUAAACGCCCAUGUGCAGGUUUUUGUUUUGACACAACUUUUCAGCCCAUUUGGAUGAAUAAAGAAACCUGAUUGCCGGA